AGUGAGGGUGGCUGCGUGUUUCCGGAAGACGUGGCGGCUCUCGCCUGGGCUGUUUCCCGGCUUCAUUUCUCCCGACUCAGCUUCCCACCCUGGGCUUUCCGAGGUGCUGUCGCCGCUGUCCCCACCACUGCAGCCAUGAUCUCCUUAACGGACACGCAGAAAAUUGGAAUGGGAUUAACAGGAUUUGGAGUGUUUUUCCUGUUCUUUGGAAUGAUUCUCUUUUUUGACAAAGCACUACUGGCUAUUGGAAAUGUUUUAUUUGUAGCCGGCUUGGCUUUUGUAAUUGGUUUAGAAAGAACAUUCAGAUUCUUCUUCCAAAAACAUAAAAUGAAAGCUACAGGUUUUUUUCUGGGUGGUGUAUUUGUAGUCCUUAUUGGUUGGCCUUUGAUAGGCAUGAUCUUCGAAAUUUAUGGAUUUUUUCUCUUGUUCAGGGGCUUCUUUCCUGUCGUUGUUGGCUUUAUUAGAAGAGUGCCAGUCCUUGGAUCCCUCCUAAAUUUACCUGGAAUUAGAUCAUUUGUAGAUAAAGUUGGAGAAAGCAACAAUAUGGUAUAACAACAAGUGAAUUUGAAGACUCAUUUAAAAUAUUGUGUUAUUUAUAAAGUCAUUUGAAGAAUAUUCAGCACAAAAUUAAAUUACAUGAAAUAGCUUGUAAUGUUCUUUACAGGAGUUUAAAACGUAUAGCCUACAAAGUACCAGCAGCAAAUUAGCAAAGAAGCAGUGAAAACAGGCUUCUACUCAAGUGAACUAAGAAGAAGUCAGCAAGCAAACUGAGAGAGGUGAAAUCCAUGUUAAUGAUGCUUAAGAAACUCUUGAAGGCUAUUUGUGUUGUUUUUCCACAAUGUGCGAAACUCAGCCAUCCUUAGAGAACUGUGGUGCCUGUUUCUUUUCUUUUUAUUUUGAAGGCUCAGGAGCAUCCAUAGGCAUUUGCUUUUUAGAAAUGUCCACUGCAAUGGCAAAAAUAUUUCCAGUUGCACUGUAUCUCUGGAAGUGAUGCAUGAAUUCGAUUGGAUUGUGUCAUUUUAAAGUAUUAAAACCAAGGAAACCCCAAUUUUGAUGUAUGGAUUACUUUUUUUUGUAAACAUGGUUAAAAUAAAACUUUUGUGGUUCUUCUGAAUCUUAAUAUUUCAAAGCCAGGUGAAAAUCUGAACUAGAUAUUCUUUGUUGGAAUAUGCAAAGGUCAUUCUUUACUAACUUUUAGUUACUAAAUUAUAGCUAAGUUUUGUCAGCAGCAUACUCCGGAAAGUCUCAUACUUCUUGGGAGUCUGCCCUCCUAAGUAUCUGUCUAUAUCAUUCAUUACGUGUAAGUAUUUAACAAAAAAGCAUUCUUGACCAUGAAUGAAGUAGUUUGUUUCAUAGCUUGUCUCAUUGAAUAGUAUUAUUGAAGAUACUAAAUGAUGCAAACCAAAUGGAUUUUUUCCAUGUCAUGAUGUAAUUUUUCUUUCUUCUUUCUUUUUUUUAAAUUUUAGCAGUGGCUUAUUAUUUGUUUUUCAUAAAUUAAAAUAACUUUUGAUAAUGUUUACUUUAAGACAUGUAACAUGUUAAAAGGUUAAACUUAUGGCUAUUUUUAAAGGGCUAUUCAUUUAAUCUGAGUUUUCCCUUAUUUUCAGCUUUUUCCUAGCAUAUAAUAGUCAUUAAGCAUGACAUAUCCUUCAUAUGAUCACUCAUCUUGAGUUAAUUAGAAAAUACCUGAGUUCACGUGCUAAAGUCAUUUCACUGUAAUAAACUGACUGUGGUUUCUUAAGAACAUGACACUAAAAAAAAAGUGUUUUUUUUCCACCGUUGCUGAUUAUUAGACAGUAGGAAAUAGCUGUUUUCUUUAGUUUUACAAGAUGUGACAGCUUUAGUGGUAGAUGUAGGGAAACAUUUCAACAGCCAUAGUACUAUUUGUUUUACCACUGAUUGCACUGUUUUGUUUUUUUAACAGUUGCAAAGCUUUUUAAUGCAUAAAAGUAUAAUUGAAAUCUGUGGUAUUUAUUUACAAACAUGUCUACAAAAAUAGAUUACAGCUUAUUUUAUUUUUAGUUAAAUCUCUUAAUACACAGAGAACUCCCAAUCUUGCUCAUCUAAAUAAGGAAAGACUUGGUGUAUAGUGUGAUGGUUUAGUCUUAAGGAUUAAGACAUUUUUGGUACUUGCAUUUGACUUACGAUGUAUCUGUGAAAAUGGGAUGAUAUUGACAAAUGGAGACUCCUACCUCAAUAGUUAAUGGAAUAAUAAGAGGCUACUGUUGUGUCUAAUGUUCUUCAAAAAAGUAAUAUCCUCACUUGGAGAGUGUCAAAUACAUACUUUGAGGAUUGACUUUAUAUAAGGUGCCCUGUAGAACUCUGUUACACAUAUUUUUGACCCAUAUUAUUUACAAUGUCUUGAUAAUUCUACCUUUUUAGAGCAAGAAUAGUAUCUGCUAAUGUAAGGGACAUCUGUAUUUAACUCCUUUGUAGACAUGAAUUUCUAUCAAAAUGUUCUUUGCACUGUAACAGAGAUUCCUUUUUUCAAUAAUCUUAAUUCAAAAGCAUUAUUAGACUUGAAAGGGUUUGAUAAUCUCCCAGUCCUUAGUAAAGAUUGAGAGAGGCUGGAGCAGUUUUCAGUUUUAAAUGAGUCUGCAGUUAAUAUCAAAUGUGAGUUUGGGACUGCCUGGCAACAUUUAUAUUUCUUAUUCAGAACCCUUGAUGAGACUAUUUUUAAACAUACUAGUCUGCUGAUAGAAAGCACUAUACAUCCUAUUGUUUCUUUCUUUCCAAAAUCAGCCUUCUGUCUGUAACAAAAAUGUACUUUAUAGAGAUGGAGGAAAAGGUCUAAUACUACAUAGCCUUAAGUGUUUCUGUCAUUGUUCAAGUGUAUUUUCUGUAACAGAAACAUAUUUGGAAUGUUUUUCUUUUCCCCUUAUAAAUUGUAAUUCCUGAAAUACUGCUGCUUUAAAAAGUCCCACUGUCAGAUUAUAUUAUCUAACAAUUGAAUAUUGUAAAUAUACUUGUCUUACCUCUCAAUAAAAGGGUACUUUUCUAUUAAUUGGUGGUCAAGUAUAUCUGUGUUAUGAAGUUCUAAAAGCUAAUUUAGCAUUGCAAAAUAACCUCAUUUUUAAAAAAUUAGCCUUAUAUGCAGUGUUCUAUUUAUCAAAUGAUCUUCACAUCUUUCAUUUCCAAAUUGUUGAAAUGUACUAAUGAAUACAAAUAGACUUCAAGUAAGCAAAAAUGUUCUUAAUUUUGAAAACUGUAAAAUAAAGUCACUUACCUUGGGCAAUAUGCUAUUUUUUAAAAA